ACGUGCGCCCGCGCCCGGCAGGCGUUCAGGGAAGCGCGGCCACGCCUGGGCCGGCCACCAUUUCCCGGGCGCCGCGGCGGCGCCGACUCGCGGGCAGCGGCCCCUCAGUGCGCCCAGCCGGGCCCCCGAACGCCGGGAGCAUGAGCGCGGGCUCGGAGCGCGGGGCGGCGGCAACCCCCGGGGGUUUGCCCGCGCCCUGCGCCUCGAAGGUGGAGCUGCGGCUCAGCUGCCGGCACCUGCUGGACCGCGACCCGCUCACCAAGUCCGACCCCAGCGUGGCGUUGCUGCAGCAGGCGCAGGGCCAGUGGGUGCAGGUGGGCAGAACCGAGGUGGUCCGGAGCAGCCUGCAUCCCGUGUUCUCCAAGGUCUUCACGGUGGACUACUACUUCGAGGAGGUGCAGAGGCUGCGCUUUGAGGUGUACGACACGCAUGGGCCCAGCGGCUUCAGCUGUCAGGAGGACGAUUUCCUGGGGGGCAUGGAGUGCACCCUGGGGCAGAUUGUGGCCCAGAAGAAGGUGACCCGCCCGCUGCUGCUCAAGUUUGGCAGGAACGCUGGCAAGUCCACCAUCACGGUGAUCGCCGAGGACAUCUCGGGGAACAACGGCUACGUGGAGCUCUCCUUCCGGGCCAGGAAGCUGGACGACAAGGACCUCUUCAGCAAGUCCGACCCCUUCCUGGAGCUCUACAGGGUCAACGACGACCAGGGCUUGCAGCUGGUGUACAGGACGGAGGUGGUGAAGAACAACCUGAACCCGGUGUGGGAGGCCUUCAAAGUCUCUCUGAGUUCCCUCUGCAGCUGCGAGGAGACAAGGCCUCUAAAGUGCCUGGUCUGGGAUUACGACUCUCGAGGAAAGCACGACUUCAUCGGAGAAUUCUCUACCACCUUCGAGGAGAUGCAGAAGGCCUUUGAGGAGGGGCAGGCCCAGUGGGACUGUGUGAACCCCAAAUACAAGCAGAAGAGACGCAGUUAUAAGAACUCAGGAGUGGUCGUCCUGGCUGACCUCAAGUUCCACAGGGUGUACUCCUUCCUGGACUAUAUCAUGGGCGGCUGCCAGAUCCACUUCACCGUGGCCAUUGACUUCACCGCCUCCAAUGGAGACCCGCGGAACAGCUGCUCCCUGCACUACAUCAACCCCUACCAGCCGAACGAGUACCUGAAGGCACUGGUGUCCGUGGGCGAGAUCUGCCAGGACUAUGACAGUGACAAGAGGUUUUCCGCUUUGGGGUUUGGAGCCCGGAUCCCUCCCAAGUAUGAGGUGUCCCAUGACUUUGCCAUCAAUUUCAACCCUGAGGACGAUGAGUGUGAAGGCAUCCAGGGCGUGGUGGAGGCCUACCAGAACUGCCUGCCCAGGGUCCAGCUCUACGGCCCCACCAACGUGGCGCCCAUCAUCUCCAAGGUGGCACGCGUGGCGGCGGCCGAGGAGAGCACCGGGAAAGCCUCUUAGAGACGGGGUUUCACCGUGUUAGCGAGGAUGGUCUCGAUCUCCUGACCUCGUGAUCCACCCGCCUCGGCCUCCCAAAGUGCUGGGAUUACAGGUGUGAGCCGCCGCGCCCGGCCCAAAAUAAUUUUAAACUCACCAAAAAGUUACAAGAGCUCUGAGGUCCUGCAACCCGUGAGGCCAACAGCUGCUCACACAUUGCGCUCCUGCUUCACGUCUGUGUAGUUGUUGUAUUUGUAUGUUUUCUUUUUCAAUUUUUUUUUUUUUUUUUGAGAUAGAGUCCUGCUCUGUCACCCAAGCUGUAGUGGUGCAAUCUCGGCUCACUGCAAGCUCCACCCUCCGAGUUCAAGCAAUUCUCCUGCCUCAGCCUCCCGAGUAGCUGGGAUUACAGGCUCCCGCCACCACGCCCGGCUAAUUUUUUGUAUUUUUAGUAGAGACGGGGUUUCACAGUCUUGGCCAGGCUGGUCUUAAACUCCUGACCUUGUGAUCCACCCGCCUCGGCCUCCCAAAGUGCUGGGAUUACAGGAGUGAGCCACCGCGCCCAGCCCAAAUUUUUUUUAUUGUGAUAAAAUAUGCACAGUUUAAAAUUUACCAUUGUAACCAUUUUUUUCUUUUCUUUUUUUUUUUUUUUUUUUGAGAUGGAGUUUUACUCUUGUCACCCAGGCUGGAGUGCAGUGACGUGAUCUCGGCUCACUGCAAGCUCCGCCUCCCGGGUUCACGCCAUUCUCCUGACUCAGCCUCCUGAGUAGCUGGGAGUACAGGCGCCCGCCACCAUACCCGGCUAAUUUUUAUAUUUUUGUAGAGAUGGGGUUUCACUGUCUUGGCCAGGCUGGUCUCAAACUCCUGACCUCAAGUGAUCUGCCUGCCUCAGCCUCCCAAAGUGCUGGGAUGGGAUUACAGGUGUGAGCCGCCGCACCUGGCCUGUAACCAUUUUAUUGUAUCCAGUUCAGAGGCACGAGGUACAUUCAUGAUGAUCAAACAUCACCCGUCUACUUACAUCUUCAAGCCAAAUGGGAACCCUAUAUCUGUUUGCAUCUAUUUUUAAUUUAUACAGAUAGUAUCGUGAUAAAGACUUUGAUGCUUUUUAAAAAACUUGGCACUGCACACACACAUUUGUGAACCGUCCGAGAGCACGUUGCAACAUCACGGUUUUACCUCUUAAUAUUUUUUUUUUUUUGAGAUGGAGUCUCGCUCUUCACCCAGGCUGGAGUGCAGUGGCGCGAUCUUGGUUCACUGCAAGCUCCGCCUCCCGGGUUCACGCCAUUCUCCUGCCUCAGCCUCCCAAAUAGCUGGGACUACAGGCGCCCGCCACCACGCCCGGCUAAUUUUUUGUAUUUUUAGUAGAGACGGGGUUUCACUGUGUUAGCCAGGAUGGUCUCGAUCUCCUGACCUCGUGAUCCGCCCACCUCGGCCUCCCAAAGUGCUGGGAUUACAGGCGUGAGCCACCGCGCCCGGCCUACCUCUUACUAUUUCAGUGUAUAUUUCCUAAGAUCAAAGAUAUUCUCUUGUAUAACCAUAGCACAAAUACAGAUUUCAGGAAAUUGAAUUUAGAUACAAUCCUUUUAUCUAAUACAUAGACUAUAUUCCAAUUUCAUUCAUUGGCACAAUCAUAACUUUCAAAGCAGUAUUGUUCCUGGCCCAGGAGCCAGUCCGGAGUCGAGGAUUGCGUUCAGCUGUUAUGUUCCUGUGUGGCUGGGAAGCGGGUCUCAGACGGUUUCAUCUGUAAAUGUCAGUAUCAGCGUCUAAUAAAGAUAAGCCUCUUUUUAAGCA